AGAGCUCGCCUCCCUCCGCCUCAGACUGUUUUGGUAGCAACGGCAACGGCGGCGGCGCGUUUCGGCCCGGCUCCCGGCGGCUCCUUGGUCUCGGCGGGCCUCCCCGCCCCUUCGUCGUCCUCCUUCUCCCCCUCGCCAGCCCGGGCGCCCCUCCGGCCGCGCCAACCCGCGCCUCCCCGCUCGGCGCCCGCGCGUCCCCGCCGCGUUCCGGCGUCUCCUUGGCGCGCCCGGCUCCCGGCUGUCCCCGCCCGGCGUGCGAGCCGGUGUAUGGGCCCCUCACCAUGUCGCUGAAGCCCCAGCAGCAGCAGCAGCAGCAGCAGCAGCAGCAGCAGCAGCAACAGCAGCAGCAGCAGCAGCAGCAGCAGCCGCCGCCCGCGGCUGCCAAUGUCCGCAAGCCCGGCGGCAGCGGCCUUCUAGCGUCGCCCGCCGCCGCGCCUUCGCCGUCCUCGUCCUCGGUCUCCUCGUCCUCGGCCACGGCUCCCUCCUCGGUGGUCGCGGCGACCUCCGGCGGCGGGAGGCCCGGCCUGGGCAGAGGUCGAAACAGUAACAAAGGACUGCCUCAGUCUACGAUUUCUUUUGAUGGAAUCUAUGCAAAUAUGAGGAUGGUUCAUAUACUUACAUCAGUUGUUGGCUCCAAAUGUGAAGUACAAGUGAAAAAUGGAGGUAUAUAUGAAGGAGUUUUUAAAACUUACAGUCCGAAGUGUGAUUUGGUACUUGAUGCCGCACAUGAGAAAAGUACAGAAUCCAGUUCGGGGCCGAAACGUGAAGAAAUAAUGGAGAGUAUUUUGUUCAAAUGUUCAGACUUUGUUGUGGUACAGUUUAAAGAUAUGGACUCCAGUUAUGCAAAAAGAGAUGCUUUUACUGACUCUGCUAUCAGUGCUAAAGUGAAUGGCGAACACAAAGAGAAGGACCUGGAGCCCUGGGAUGCAGGUGAACUCACAGCCAAUGAGGAACUUGAGGCUUUGGAAAAUGACGUAUCUAAUGGAUGGGAUCCCAAUGAUAUGUUUCGAUAUAAUGAAGAAAAUUAUGGUGUAGUGUCUACGUAUGAUAGCAGUUUAUCUUCGUAUACAGUGCCCUUAGAAAGAGAUAACUCAGAAGAAUUUUUAAAACGGGAAGCAAGGGCAAACCAGUUAGCAGAAGAAAUUGAGUCAAGUGCCCAGUACAAAGCUCGAGUGGCCCUGGAAAAUGAUGAUAGGAGUGAGGAAGAAAAAUACACAGCAGUUCAGAGAAAUUCCAGUGAACGUGAGGGGCACAGCAUAAACACUAGGGAAAAUAAAUAUAUUCCUCCUGGACAAAGAAAUAGAGAAGUCAUAUCCUGGGGAAGUGGGAGACAGAAUUCACCGCGUAUGGGCCAGCCUGGAUCGGGCUCCAUGCCAUCAAGAUCCACUUCUCACACUUCAGAUUUCAACCCGAAUUCUGGUUCAGACCAAAGAGUAGUUAAUGGAGGUGUUCCCUGGCCAUCGCCUUGCCCAUCUCCUUCCUCUCGCCCACCUUCUCGCUACCAGUCAGGUCCCAACUCUCUUCCACCUCGGGCAGCCACCCCUACACGGCCGCCCUCCAGGCCCCCCUCGCGGCCAUCCAGACCCCCGUCUCACCCCUCUGCUCAUGGUUCUCCAGCUCCUGUCUCUACUAUGCCUAAACGCAUGUCUUCAGAAGGGCCUCCAAGGAUGUCCCCAAAGGCCCAGCGACAUCCUCGAAAUCACAGAGUUUCUGCUGGGAGGGGUUCCAUAUCCAGUGGCCUAGAAUUUGUAUCCCACAACCCACCCAGUGAAGCAGCUACUCCUCCAGUAGCAAGGACCAGUCCCUCGGGGGGAACGUGGUCAUCAGUGGUCAGUGGGGUUCCAAGAUUAUCCCCUAAAACUCAUAGACCCAGGUCUCCCAGACAGAACAGUAUUGGAAAUACCCCCAGUGGGCCAGUUCUUGCUUCUCCCCAAGCUGGUAUUAUUCCAACUGAAGCUGUUGCCAUGCCUAUUCCAGCUGCAUCUCCUACGCCUGCUAGUCCUGCAUCGAACAGAGCUGUUACCCCUUCUAGUGAGGCUAAAGAUUCCAGGCUUCAAGAUCAGAGGCAGAACUCUCCUGCAGGGAAUAAAGAAAAUAUUAAACCCAAUGAAACAUCACCUAGCUUCUCAAAAGCUGAAAACAAAGGUAUAUCACCAGUUGUUUCUGAACAUAGAAAACAGAUUGAUGAUUUAAAGAAAUUUAAGAAUGAUUUUAGGUUACAGCCAAGUUCUACUUCUGAAUCUAUGGAUCAACUACUAAACAAAAAUAGAGAGGGAGAAAAAUCAAGAGAUUUGAUCAAAGACAAAAUUGAACCAAGUGCUAAGGAUUCUUUCAUUGAAAAUAGCAGCAGCAACUGUACCAGUGGCAGCAGCAAGCCGAAUAGCCCCAGCAUUUCCCCUUCAAUACUUAGUAACACGGAGCACAAGAGGGGACCUGAGGUCACUUCCCAAGGGGUUCAGACUUCCAGCCCAGCAUGUAAACAAGAGAAAGACGAUAAGGAAGAGAAGAAAGACGCAGCUGAGCAAGUUAGGAAAUCAACAUUGAAUCCCAAUGCAAAGGAGUUCAACCCACGUUCCUUCUCUCAGCCAAAGCCUUCUACUACCCCAACUUCACCUCGGCCUCAAGCACAACCUAGCCCAUCUAUGGUGGGUCAUCAACAGCCAACUCCAGUUUAUACUCAGCCUGUUUGUUUUGCACCAAAUAUGAUGUAUCCAGUCCCAGUGAGCCCAGGCGUGCAACCUUUAUACCCAAUACCUAUGACGCCCAUGCCAGUGAAUCAAGCCAAGACAUAUAGAGCAGGUAAAGUACCAAAUAUGCCCCAACAGCGGCAAGACCAGCAUCAUCAGAGUGCCAUGAUGCACCCAGCGUCAGCAGCGGGCCCACCGAUUGCAGCCACCCCACCAGCUUACUCCACGCAAUAUGUUGCCUACAGUCCUCAGCAGUUCCCAAAUCAGCCCCUUGUUCAGCAUGUGCCACAUUAUCAGUCUCAGCAUCCUCAUGUCUAUAGUCCUGUAAUACAGGGUAAUGCUAGAAUGAUGGCACCACCAACACACGCCCAGCCUGGUUUAGUAUCUUCUUCAGCAACUCAGUACGGGGCUCAUGAGCAGACGCAUGCGAUGUAUGCAUGUCCCAAAUUACCAUACAACAAGGAGACAAGCCCUUCUUUCUACUUUGCCAUUUCCACGGGCUCCCUUGCUCAGCAGUAUGCGCACCCUAACGCUACCCUGCACCCACAUACUCCACACCCUCAGCCUUCAGCUACCCCCACUGGACAGCAGCAAAGCCAACAUGGUGGAAGUCAUCCUGCACCCAGUCCUGUUCAGCACCAUCAGCACCAGGCCGCCCAGGCUCUCCAUCUGGCCAGUCCACAGCAGCAGUCAGCCAUUUACCACGCGGGGCUUGCGCCAACUCCACCCUCCAUGACACCUGCCUCCAACACGCAGUCGCCACAGAAUAGUUUCCCAGCAGCACAACAGACUGUCUUUACGAUCCAUCCUUCUCACGUUCAGCCGGCGUAUACCAACCCACCCCACAUGGCCCACGUACCUCAGGCUCAUGUACAGUCAGGAAUGGUUCCUUCUCAUCCAACUGCCCAUGCGCCAAUGAUGCUAAUGACGACACAGCCACCCGGCGGUCCCCAGGCCGCCCUCGCUCAAAGUGCACUACAGCCCAUUCCAGUCUCGACAACAGCGCAUUUCCCCUAUAUGACGCACCCUUCAGUACAAGCCCACCACCAACAGCAGUUGUAAGGCUGCCCUGGAGGAACCGAAAGGCCAAAUUCCCUCCUCCCUUCUACUGCUUCUACCAACUGGAAGCACAGAAAACUAGAAUUUCAUUUAUUUUGUUUUUAAAAUAUAUAUGUUGAUUUCUUGUAACAUCCAAUAGGAAUGCUAACAGUUCACUUGCAGUGGAAGAUACUUGGACCGAGUAGAGGCAUUUAGGAACUUGGGGGCUAUUCCAUAAUUCCAUAUGCUGUUUCAGAGUCCCGCAGGUACCCCAGCUCUGCUUGCCGAAACUGGAAGUUAUUUAUUUUUUAAUAACCCUUGAAAGUCAUGAACACAUCAGCUAGCAAAAGAAGUAACAAGAGUGAUUCUUGCUGCUAUUACUGCUAAAAAAAAAAAAAAAAAAAAAUCAAGACUUGGAACGCCCUUUUACUAAACUUGACAAAGUUUCAGUAAAUUCUUACCGUCAAACUGACGGAUUAUUAUUUAUAAAUCAAGUUUGAUGAGGUGAUCACUGUCUACAGUGGUUCAACUUUUAAGUUAAGGGAAAAACUUUUACUUUGUAGAUAAUAUAAAAUAAAAACUUAAAAAAAAUUUAAAAAAUAAAAAAAGUUUUAAAAACUGA